ACUGGCCCUGUCCUUCCAUCUGCCCAGAGAGGAGCAUCUGGAUCAAGGUGCUGGCCAUGUCCCAGCUGGUGGAAUGCGUCCCCAACUUUUCGGAGGGGAAGAACCAGGAGGUGAUCGACGCCAUCUCUGGAGCCAUCACACAGACCCCGGGCUGCGUGCUGCUGGAUGUGGACGCAGGCCCUUCCACCAACCGCACCGUGUACACCUUCGUGGGGCCGCCGGAGUGCGUGGUGGAGGGGGCCCUCAACGCUGCCCGGGUAGCUUCCCGACUUAUCGACAUGAGCAGGCACCAAGGAGAGCACCCCCGCAUGGGGGCCCUAGACGUCUGCCCCUUCAUCCCCGUGAGGGGCGUCAGCGUGGAUGAGUGUGUGCUCUGCGCCCAGGCCUUUGGCCAGAGGCUGGCAGAGGAGCUGGACGUGCCAGUUUACCUGUACGGCGAGGCAGCCAGGAUGGACAGUCGCCGGACCCUGCCGGCCAUCCGGGCCGGGGAGUACGAGGCCCUCCCUAAGAAGCUCCAGCAGGCCGACUGGGCGCCCGACUUUGGUCCCAGCUCCUUUGUCCCCAGUUGGGGGGCCACGGCCACGGGGGCGAGGAAGUUCCUCAUUGCUUUUAACAUCAACCUGCUCGGCACAAAGGAGCAAGCCCACCGCAUCGCGCUCAACCUGCGGGAGCAGGGCCGCGGGAAGGACCAGCCAGGACGUCUGAAGAAAGUUCAGGGCAUUGGCUGGUACCUGGAUGAGAAGAACCUGGCUCAGGUGUCCACCAAUCUUCUGGACUUUGAGGUCACGGCACUGCACACGGUCUACGAGGAGACCUGCCGAGAAGCACAGGAGCUGAGCCUCCCAGUGGUGGGCUCACAGCUGGUGGGCCUGGUGCCCCUGAAGGCUCUGCUGGAUGCGGCCGCCUUCUACUGCGAGAAGGAGAACCUCUUCAUCCUGGAGGAGGAGCAGCGGAUCAGGCUGGUGGUGAGCCGGCUGGGCCUGGACUCCCUGUGCCCCUUCAGCCCUAAGGAGCGGAUCAUCGAGUACCUGGUCCCUGAGCGCGGGCCUGAGCGAGGCCUGGGCAGCAAGUCCCUGCGCGCCUUCGUGGGGGAGGUGGGUGCCCGCUCUGCGGCCCCCGGGGGCGGCUCGGUGGCGGCGGCCGCUGCGGCCAUGG